AGGCCGAGCGGGAGGUCGGGGCUGCGGGCGCUCGCUGGUGGCGGACCCGGAGGCUGCUGCGGCGCCGGGGCUCCGUGGCCUGGAUUGAAUCCGAUCGGGAGCCAUGAGCGUGGACAAAGCUGAGCUAUGCGGGUCUCUGCUCACCUGGUUACAGACGUUCCACGUUCCGUCUCCCUGUGCCAGCCCUCAGGACCUGAGCAGCGGCCUUGCCGUAGCCUAUGUGCUGAACCAGAUAGACCCCUCCUGGUUCAACGAGGCAUGGCUCCAGGGCAUCUCGGAAGAUCCAGGUCCCAACUGGAAGCUGAAGGUGACAAGUGGACUCCUGAUUAGAGGACAGACUGGUGAAGAGAUGACCAGGGACGGGCCAGCUAGGCACAUGUCCUGGGUGAUGGGCAGGAAGAGGGACAGAUGUCUGGUCAGCAAUCUGAAGAUGGUCUUACGGAGCCUAGUAGAGUACUCCCAGGAUGUCCUGGCGCAUCCUGUGUCAGAAGAGCAUCUCCCAGAUGUGAGCCUCAUUGGAGAGUUCUCAGACCCGGCAGAGCUCGGCAAGCUGCUUCAGCUGGUGCUGGGCUGUGCCAUCAGUUGCGAGAAAAAGCAGGACCACAUCCAGAGAAUCAUGACGCUGGAAGAAUCGGUUCAGCAUGUGGUGAUGGAAGCCAUCCAAGAGCUCAUGACCAAAGACACUCCUGACUCCCUGUCACCAGAGACGUAUGGCAACUUUGACAGCCAGUCCCGCAGGUACUAUUUCCUAAGUGAGGAGGCUGAGGAGGGGGACGAAUUACAGCAGCGCUGUCUGGAUCUGGAGCGGCAGCUGAUGCUCCUGUCAGAGGAGAAGCAGAGCCUGGCGCAAGAGAAUGCAGGGCUGCGGGAGCGGAUGGGCCGGCCUGAAGGCGAGGGUACCCCAGGUCUCACUGCCAAGAAGCUGCUGCUGCUGCAAUCCCAGCUGGAGCAGUUGCAGGAGGAGAACUUCAGGCUGGAGAGUGGCAGGGAGGAUGAGCGCCUGCGCUGUGCCGAGCUGGAGAGGGAGGUUGCGGAGCUGCAGCACCGGAACCAGGCGCUGACUAGCCUGGCCCAGGAGGCACAGGCCCUGAAGGAUGAGAUGGAUGAACUACGGCAGUCUUCGGAGCGUGCUGGGCAGCUGGAGGCCACGCUGACCAGUUGCCGGCGCCGCUUGGGCGAGCUGAGGGAGCUGCGGCGGCAGGUGCGGCAGCUGGAGGAACGCAACGCCGGCCACGCCGAGCGCACGCGACAACUGGAGGAUGAGCUACGCCGAGCGGGCUCCCUGCGCGCCCAGCUGGAGGCGCAGCGGCGGCAGGUGCAGGAACUGCAGGGCCAGCGGCAGGAGGAGGCCAUGAAGGCCGAGAAAUGGCUAUUUGAAUGCCGCAACCUGGAGGAAAAGUAUGAGUCGGUGACAAAGGAGAAGGAGCGGCUGUUGGCGGAGCGGGACUCCUUGCGGGAGGCCAAUGAGGAGCUGCGCUGCGCCCAGCUGCAGCCGCGGGGGUUGACCCAGGCCGAUCCCUCACUGGAUCCCACCUCCACACCCGUGGAUAACUUAGCCGCAGAGAUCCUGCCUGCGGAGCUCAGGGAGACGCUCCUGCGGCUUCAGCUGGAGAACAAGCGGCUGUGCAGGCAGGAGGCGGCCGACCGGGAGCGGCAGGAGGAGCUGCAGCGCCACCUGGAGGAUGCCAACCGCGCGCGCCACGGGUUGGAGACGCAGCACCGGCUGAACCAGCAGCAGCUAUCCGAGCUGCGGGCCCAGGUGGAGGACCUGCAGAAAGCCCUGCAGGAGCAGGGGGGCAAGACUGAAGAUUCCAUUUUGCUGAAAAGGAAGCUGGAGGAACAUUUGCAGAAGCUUCAUGAGGCAGAUCUGGAGUUGCAGAGGAAGCGGGAGUACAUUGAGGAGCUGGAGCCACCCACUGACAGCAGCACAGCCCGGCGGAUCGAGGAGCUGCAGCAUAACUUGCAGAAGAAGGACGCGGACUUGCGGGCCAUGGAGGAGCGAUACCGCCGCUACGUGGACAAGGCCCGCAUGGUCAUGCAGACCAUGGAACCCAAGCAGCGGCCAGCUGCGGGGGCACCUCCAGAACUCCAUUCCCUGAGGACACAGCUCCGAGAACGGGAUGUCCGCAUCCGACACCUGGAGAUGGACUUUGAGAAAAGCCGAAGUCAGCGGGAGCAGGAAGAAAAGCUGCUCAUCAGUGCCUGGUAUAAUAUGGGCAUGGCCUUGCAGCAGCGAGCUGGGGAGGAGCGGGCGCCUGCCCAUGCCCAGUCAUUCCUGGCACAGCAGCGGCUGGCAACCAAUUCUCGCCGUGGACCCUUGGGACGCCUGGCAUCUCUGAACCUUCGCCCCACUGACAAGCACUGACAGACCUCACAAUCAAGCCAGCCUGGGCUCCACCCACCCUGGCUUCCUCCAGCUCACAUGGCGCCCAGCACUGGGCUUCAGCCAGGUGCUCGAGAGCUUUGAGGCCAUGAUCUCUGCUCUUCCCUCUCCCAGAUUGGUGGGGAGGGAGGGCGGGAGGUAGAUAUAGGCCUGUUCUUUUUAGCAAUGUGAUUCUUGUUGUUGAUUCUCUCUCUGGAGUUCAUGUGCUGCCUCAGGAGACUCUGAUUUUAUAUUUGAGAAAAAUAAAGGCGUUCAAUCUGC